AGUGGUGAGUGUGCGGAGCGCCGAGGCUCGCGUUCCGCCGCUGCUUCCGUCGCCGGGGCGGGCGCCGCGGUGUCCCUGCCGAGCGUGAGCCCCGAACUGUCACCGCGCCGAGCCCCAGCCUCAUCCGUCGGUGUCCGCGGUCCGAGCUUUCCCCGCCUCGCUGGCGGCCCGCGCUCUCCCCCGCCGUGCGCGUUCGCCGCUGUGGCCUGUAGCUACCUCGCCUCGCUGCUUUGUCUCCGCUGCUCUUGCCGUCCUUCCCGCGGCCUUCUGCGGGCGGGGCUGUCGGCUGUCGCUUUGCUGCUCCGCGACGGCGGCCUUGAGUCUCGCUCCCCCGGUGGGAAACGUAGAACUGGUUACUCGCCACCUUAGGCGGUGGGGUUUGAAUGAGAGCGGUGCCUCGGUAGGUCGUCAGAAAGUUACAGUCGCCCAUCUGAGCGUUUGUAAGAGAUGGAGGCAGGAGUGGUGAGGUUGAUUCUUCACCACACUGAAACCAUUAGGAAAAAUCCUUGUGGUUAACAGCAGAGGCUUCAGAGUGUAACCUGUACUCGGGCCUAGAAAUUAUUUAAAAUGGCGACUGAUACGUCUCAAGGUGAACUCGUCCAUCCUAAGGCACUCCCACUUAUAGUAGGAGCUCAGCUGAUCCACGCGGACAAGUUAGGUGAGAAGGUAGAAGAUAGCACCAUGCCGAUUCGUCGAACUGUGAAUUCUACCCGGGAAACUCCUCCCAAAAGCAAGCUUGCUGAAGGGGAGGAAGAAAAGCCAGAACCAGACAUAAGUUCAGAGGAAUCUGUCUCCACUGUAGAAGAACAAGAGAAUGAAACUCCACCUGCUACUUCGAGUGAGGCAGAGCAGCCAAAGGGGGAACCUGAGAAUGAAGAGAAGGAAGAAAAUAAGUCUUCUGAGGAAACCAAAAAGGAUGAGAAAGAUCAGUCUAAAGAAAAGGAGAAGAAAGUGAAAAAAACAAUUCCUUCCUGGGCUACCCUUUCUGCCAGCCAGCUAGCCAGGGCCCAGAAACAAACACCGAUGGCUUCUUCCCCACGUCCCAAGAUGGAUGCAAUCUUAACUGAGGCCAUUAAGGCAUGCUUCCAGAAGAGUGGUGCAUCAGUGGUUGCUAUUCGAAAAUACAUCAUCCAUAAGUAUCCUUCUCUGGAGCUGGAGAGAAGGGGUUAUCUCCUUAAACAAGCACUGAAAAGAGAAUUAAAUAGAGGAGUCAUCAAACAGGUUAAAGGAAAAGGUGCUUCUGGAAGUUUUGUUGUGGUUCAGAAAUCAAGAAAAACACCUCAGAAAUCCAGAAACAGAAAGAAUAGGAGCUCUGCAGUGGAUCCAGAACCACAAGUAAAAUUGGAGGAUGUCCUCCCACUGGCCUUUACUCGCCUUUGUGAACCUAAAGAAGCUUCCUACAGUCUCAUCAGGAAAUAUGUGUCUCAGUAUUAUCCUAAGCUUAGAGUGGACAUCAGGCCUCAGCUGUUGAAGAACGCUCUGCAGAGAGCAGUAGAGAGGGGCCAGUUAGAACAGAUAACUGGCAAAGGUGCUUCGGGGACAUUCCAGCUGAAGAAAUCAGGGGAGAAACCCCUGCUUGGUGGAAGCCUGAUGGAAUAUGCAAUCUUGUCUGCCAUUGCUGCCAUGAAUGAGCCGAAGACCUGCUCUACCACUGCUCUGAAGAAGUAUGUCCUAGAGAAUCACCCAGGAACCAAUUCUAACUAUCAAAUGCAUUUGCUGAAAAAAACCCUGCAGAAAUGCGAAAAGAAUGGGUGGAUGGAACAGAUCUCUGGGAAAGGGUUCAGUGGCACCUUCCAGCUCUGUUUUCCCUAUUAUCCCAGCCCAGGAGUUCUGUUUCCGAAGAAAGAGCCAGAUGAUUCUAGAGAUGAGGAUGAAGAUGAAGAUGAGUCAUCAGAAGAAGACUCUGAGGAUGAAGAGCCGCCACCUAAGAGAAGGUUGCAGAAGAAAACCCCAGCCAAGUCCCCAGGGAAGGCCGCAUCUGUGAAGCAGAGAGGGUCCAAACCUGCACCUAAAGUCUCAGCUGCCCAGCGGGGGAAAGCUAGGCCCUUGCCUAAGAAAGCACCUCCUAAGGCCAAAACGCCUGCCAAGAAGACCAGACCCUCAUCCACAGUCAUCAAGAAACCUAGUGGUGGCUCCUCAAAGAAGCCUGCAACCAGUGCAAGAAAGGAAGUAAAAUUGCCGGGCAAGGGCAAAUCCACCAUGAAGAAGUCUUUCAGAGUGAAAAAGUAAAUUUUAUAGGAAAAAAGGGUAUCAUGAUGAAAUUCAAAAUCUUAUUUUCUAAGGUCAGUGUGCAUUUGUUUAGUUUUGAUGCUUUUCAAAUUACAUUAUUUUCCUCCCCUAUGAACAUUGUGGGGAGGGACUCUAAAUAAACCAGUUUAGGCAUUUGCUAGCUUUAGGUGCUUUUAUUGGUGCCUGCCCUUUUCCUUGUUCAUUUUAAUUUCUGCAAUAAUCCUGGACUUUCCUAAACUAUGUAAUGUAUACUUGUCCUUUUUCUCUGCCUCCCCCAACCCCCUGUUGUUUUUAUGGUCAGCUUUGCCUUUUUUUUUUCUUCCAAUUUUAUCUAAACAGUUGCAGAGAUUUUUAUAUUUGUAGAAAGCAUCAAGAACGGUAUGCCAGUCAGGUCCUGGAAGUAAAAUGGAGGCACAAUAUAGCACUGACUGAGUUGUAAAGCCUCCUGCCUGGAGACUUCAGUUAUAGCUGUAAUAAUUAAUCUUAUUUAUAAAAGCCACUCCACUAACCUUUUCUCUCCAACUGUAAACACAGAGACAGCUUUGGGAAUAAGCCAAAAACAGGGUGAUCUCAUUAGAUUUUGAAGAUAUAUGACUCCUUUGGGCUACAUUUCAUAUUGAUCAAUUUCUAGGUAUUUUUCACUGGCCCAAAGUAUUGCAUUCCCUUAACAGCAAGCACAAGUUCUCUAUAUCACUUGUUUUUUGUUGUUGUUGUUGUUGUCGUCGUUGUUUUGAGACGGAGUCUUGCUCAGGUGCCCCGGAGUGCAGUGGUGCAAUCUCAGCUCACUGCAACCUCCACCUCCUGGGUUCAAGCAAUUCUCCUGCUUCAGCCUCCCGAGUAGCUGGGAUUACAGGUGUGUACCACCACGCCUGGCAAUUUUUUUGUAUUUUUAGUAGAGAUGGGGUUUCGCCGUGUUGGUCAGGCUGGUCUCGAACUCCUGACCUCAGGUGAUCCGCCUGCCUCGGCCUCCCAAAGUGCUGGGAUUACAGGAGUGAGCCACUGUGCCUGGCCUAUCCCACUUGGUUUUUGACUGAAGGGGAAGUGUAGAAAUAUAUUGAUUUGUGAUUUCUGGUGUCACCUGUGUUACCAAAAAUCAAAACAAAUCUUUUUUAUUUUUUAUUAUUAUUAUUAUUUUUGAGACAGAGUCUCGCUCUGUCGCCCAGUGUGGAGUGCAGUGGUGUGAUCUUGGCUCACUGCAAACUCCGCCUCCCAGGUUCAAGCGAUUCUCCCACCUCAGCCUCCUGAGUUGGGUCCUACAGGCGCACACGACCACGCCCAGCUAAUUUUUUGUAUUUUUAGUAGAGUUGGGGUUUCACCAUGUUAGCCAGGAUGGUCUCGAUCUCCUGACCUCGUGAUCCACUCACCUCAGCCUCCCAAAAUCCUGGGGUUACAGAUGUGAGCUACCACUCACGGCCCAAAUCUUCUUGAUCAUAUGUUUAAAUAUAUUUUUUAAUAUUUGGAGCAUGAGUUGUCACUUCUUGUUUGCCUUUUUUAUAAGGAAAUGUUGGAGAGUUACAUCAUUGCUAAUGUAGAAAUGUUAAGUGGAAAAAUAUACAGUUUGGUAAAAUAAACUAGAUUCUACAUUUAUUUGUGGGUUUUUUUCCCCUCCUUUCUUUCCACAGCACUUUUGAUAUCAAGCAAGUGGCUUCCUUUUUGAGAUAUUAAAAAAAAAAAGAAAAGGAAAAAAGUAAAUGAAGCCCAACUACCUAACCCUUUCUUAUUUGUAUUUGUUUUAGUAUUGUGAAGUUGUGUUAAAUAGUACUAGCUAGAAAUACAAAUUUCUGGUUAUCAUUUCUCUUCCCUGUGGCACUUGACAUUUUAAUUGUCUUAAAGUUUUUGAAGUACAUCUUCUGGCCCCUUGAGUACUGCCAGAGGCAAAAGAUGUUUGUUUCUUAUUCAUUCCACUUUUGUCUCCUGGGAUCCCUUCUGUAGCCUAAAGUAUGGCUGGGAAAUGGACUUGAGAAGAUUGGCUUGAAUUAGAUCAUAAUCAUGUGUGAUCCCAUCAUGAAUUCAUUGGAAUUUGUGUUGCAUGUAAGGCAAUCUUUCCUGUUGUAAAUCUUCCUUUUUUAAUGUACAUAUAUUUUGAAAAAUAUGAAUAAACAUGAAAUUUUAAAAGCUGCUGAACCGUAGCUUAUAUUUAAAGGUUUUGAGUAUAGUAUAUCCUCAGAAGUAGCUAAGUGUCGCCCUCACUUUAAGUCUUUUCUACUCCUUGAAAUGAACACCAUCAUUUUCCUUUUUAAAUACAAGCUCCAGUUCAUGUGUUUUGGAAUUCUUAUAGAGGGUAAACGAUGUUUCCAGAUACAUUGAAUGCUAAUUACUUAAUGAAUCAAAGGUUUAAAAAAUCAUUUUGUAUUUUAUUAAAGACUGCUUCCAAGAUCAUAGAGUACAAUCAUGUUCAAUAAAUGUUCAAUAUUCAGAUAAGUCCUUGGACUAGAAAAAAUUACAGUACUGCAAAAGAUAACAGAUAAAUCCUAGACAUCAAAUUCUAGAAGUAAUUGUAGUAAUUACUCCUGUGCUCUCUAGCAAGUAAUGAUUCUUAAUAGUAUGGAUGUUAGGUACCUGUGCUCAGAAUUCUGUACUCUUCUGGAAUCAAAAGUUGGGAGAUUUUGGUUGGUUUCUUUGCUUUAUGAUACUGCUUUUAAAGAGACUUACUGAAUAAUCACCUGGUGGCUGUAUUGCACACCAGGCACUUAAGCACAGGCUGAGAAGUUUAGAUCAUUUAAAGUUUCUUCCAACUCUAACGUUCUGUUAACUAUAAGGACAGUUUGUUUCAGUGUGAUGUAAAGGGAAAAGACAGGAAGGUCAUCGCACUCUUCCACGAACAUCCACAACUGUCAAAGACAUACGCCUUACUUACAUUGAGAUAAAAGAAUGUUUGAUUUUUCCCUUCCAGGCAUUCCAAAGGAGCAGAACACAUUUAUAAUUUUUACUUCCAUGUUCAGAAAGGGGAACAACAAACCCCAGAGGUAAUCCCAGAAAUCUCUAGCAUGGAUCAAUAGCUUCAGUACUCUGUUGGUGGCUUAGUGACCUCAUUUACAGUGUUUCAUACACUCUGAAACUACCUACAAGCUACCUUUGAUAAAUGAGUCUCAGAAAGUGCUGGGAGAGAGAUUGUUGGCUUCUUAACCUACAAAAUGAGGAAGGAAAGAUACUAUUGUUGAGAAAUGUGGAGACCUUUCCUUAGCACUAUGACAGAAGCAUUCAUUGCACAUGGAUUCUGACUAUGCAUCCACAUGGACUUAAUUAAAGGAAACCUGGUCCUGUAUAAAUCUUAGGAAACAGGUGUAUGUUUUAAUCAUGUCUUUUGGGUAUAAUUAACAGGAAAAUGACAUGAAAACAAAACUAAACAAUCUGCUAACACCUUUUGACAUUUGUUUUUUCAUCAUUGCUGUUUUUCCAAAUUUUGUUAGCCCUUGUCAAGGUUUGCUAACCAAUUCUUAAUUAAUACUUACUUUAAAGAGCCUGUGAAAUUAUUCUCUCUCAGGCUGUGACCCUCUUGCCAUCUUGAUACGUCAUGAGAACGAAACUCACCAGCCAUGUUCAUUAAAUACUGCAUUUAACUAAGAGAAACUUUAAAAAUUUGGGAUUAUAGUUAAGGUCUCCUAUCUUUGGAACCUGAUUAAUUUAUCUUUCUUUGGAUUAAGCAAAAAUUCUAAUUUUAGCUAUGAAAGAAAAGAAAUUCUAUUCUUAAUUGGAAAAGACCAUUAAACUGUUUCCCCAGAGGUUCUGGUUGACAUUACUUUCUAGCAUGUAGAUUUUGCUUUUGCAUUUUCAUGGUGGAACAGAUGGUCACUCACUUCUGCAGAGCCAAAGCCAAGGAAGCAGAACUGUUGAAGUUUUGGCUUAGGAACCACUUGACAAAGAUUUGUUUAGAAGCCAUUACAGAUGGUUAAACAGUACCCCUAAUCAGCUGCAUUAUUUUCUUAAGAAAUUAAUCUCUACCGUCUUUAUAACUAUAUUCUUUUACUUAUUAUUUUUUUGAGAUGGAGUUUGCUGUGUCACUAAGGCUGCAGCGCAGUGGUGUGAUCUUGGCUCACUGCAGCUUUGAACUCGUGUGCUCAAGCAGUUCUCCCCACCUCAGCCUCCCAAGUAGCCAGGACUACAGGCAAGCUAAUAAAUGCCUGGCUAAUUUAUCUUUUCUAGAGAUGGGGCCUCACUGUGUUGCCCAGGCUGGUCUUGAACUCGUGGCCUCACGUGAUCUUCCCACCUGGGCUUUCCAAAGUGCCAGGAUUACAGGCGUGAGUCGCCAUACCUGGCCCUAUUCUUUCUUCUGUUCUUUUCCACAAGACUGUUAACUUCAGUGGCUUUUUUCCUGUUGGAAAACUUUCUACCUUUGAUGAUUUAAUUUUAUCAGCUUUUUAACUGUUUUAACUGUUCUUAAUUCUGUCUUGUCAACCACUGGUAUGUCAAAGGAGGCCUCAAAAGGCUGAAGCGAUUUUCCUCAAAAAUUACAACUCUUUUUUUUCCUGAUAUUGUAUAUAAUGUAUAAUUAACACUGUUCACUAUUAAAUCUUUGCUUAGCAAAAGAGAA